GUAGACCUUCUCUGAAUGUUUUGGUGAAUAAAUCUGUUCUUCAGCAACCCUACCUGCUUCUCCAAACUGCCUAAAGAGAUCCAGUACUGAUGACGCUGUUCUUCCAUCUUUACUCCCUGGAAACUAACCACGUUGUCUUCUUUCCUUCACCACCACCCAGGAGCUCAGAGAUCUAAGCUGCUUUCCAUCUUUUCUCCCAGCCCCAGGACACUGACUCUGUACAGGAUGGGGCCGUCCUCUUGCCUCCUUCUCAUCCUAAUCCCCCUUCUCCAGCUGAUCAACCCGGGGAGUACUCAGUGUUCCUUAGACUCCGUUAUGGAUAAGAAGAUCAAGGAUGUUCUCAACAGUCUAGAGUACAGUCCCUCUCCUAUAAGCAAGAAGCUCUCGUGUGCUAGUGUCAAAAGCCAAGGCAGACCGUCCUCCUGCCCUGCUGGGAUGGCUGUCACUGGCUGUGCUUGUGGCUAUGGCUGUGGUUCGUGGGAUGUUCAGCUGGAAACCACCUGCCACUGCCAGUGCAGUGUGGUGGACUGGACCACUGCCCGCUGCUGCCACCUGACCUGACAGGGAGGAGGCUGAGAACUCAGUUUUGUGACCAUGACAGUAAUGAAACCAGGGUCCCAACCAAGAAAUCUAACUCAAACGUCCCACUUCAUUUGUUCCAUUCCUGAUUCUUGGGUAAUAAAGACAAACUUUGUACCUCU